GGAAAAUACUCUGCAUACCUUAAAACAACGGCAGCUGACUUCUUACGUUGGAAGUGUUCGUCCGCUUGUCACUGAAUUGGUAAAUGUUCUUUGAAAUGAAAGUUGCCUUCAAAGUUAACUGAUUUUUUUUUUCAGGCUGAGAAUUUUUUCUCGUGGAUCUUUGUUUUGCUCUUCUAAAGGUUUGCACACACUAACAUUUUACUCUAAAACAACUAAGUUGCAUUGGAAUCUGAUGGAAUAUAUUGAAACAUAUCCGUGACCUUUGAAUUAUCAUGUGUGCUGUUUGCUGCUAAAGUGAGAACAAUAUAUUAUCCUAAAUGCUUAGAAGCACAUGGAAAAAAGGUAGGUAGAAAUAACUGUUUUGGGAGAUUUGUACUUAUUUAUUAGAAAUCUGUUUAAAUUUUUUUAUUAGGCAUUGGUGUUUUUUAUGUGGCAUUAAUCCCAAAAUAGGUCUUAAUAGGCCCUCUUCCCAUAUGUUCUCAAAAAGUACCAGGUAAGCACUUUGUAGUCACAGAACAGAAGGUUUUUGCUUUGUGUUCUUCUUCCAUCUAGGUCUAAUUCUAUUUAAACUUGACCAUGUAGCUGCUGUGAUAGAGUGAAACUCAAGUCAUCUUCUAGUGUUACCUGGGCUGGGAUAGGCUAGUAGUAUUUCUGCCUUGCCUGACUGAGGCAUGCCCUUUGUGGGCCAACUGAGUAUGUUUUAAGUAGGGAAGCAGAUGACUAUGUGGCUAUUUGGAACACUUGUAAUCUUGUGAGAGCUUCAUUCCCUUUGUUACUUAAUUAAAUUGAAACAAUUUAUUUCAGCCAGGCGCAGUGGUUCACGCCUGUAAUCCCAGCACUUUGGGUGGCCGAGGUGGGUGGAUCAUGAGGUCAGGAGUUCGAGACCAAUCUGGUCAACGUGGUGAAACCCCGUCUCUACUAAAAAUACAAAAAUUAGCUGGGCGUGGUGGCGUGCACCUAUAAUCCCAGCUGCUCGGGAGGCCGAGGCAGGAGAAUUGCUUGAACAGAGGAGAUGGAGGUUGUGGUGUGCUGAGAUCGCGCCACUGCACUCCAGCCUGGGCGACAGAACAAGACUCCGUCUCGGAAAAGAAAAAAGAAAAAAUGAAUUUAUUUGUGUAUAAACUCAGGAUAGGUUUAUCAUCUCUUGAUGAUGUGUAAAAUGUAUGUAAGUACAAAGGAUUUAUGGUUGAUGAUGACUUUUUUUUCUUCUUACAGGACCCUGAUGCUCCCAUAAGACAGAAAAUGCCCCUUGAUGAUCUGGAUAGAGAAGAUGAAGUUAGAUUACUCAAAUAUCUCUUUACUCUAAUCCGUGCUGGAAUGACAGAAGAGGCACAACGACUCUGUAAACGCUGUGGUCAAGCAUGGAGAGCUGCAACACUUGAAGGCUGGAAACUGUACCAUGACCCUAAUGUUAAUGGAGGAACAGAAUUAGAACCUGUUGAAGGGAAUCCAUAUAGACGCAUUUGGAAAAUAAGUUGCUGGAGAAUGGCAGAAGAUGAGCUUUUUAAUAGAUACGAGAGAGCAAUUUAUGCAGCUUUAAGUGGGAAUCUUAAGCAGCUGCUUCCUGUCUGUGACACCUGGGAAGACACAGUUUGGGCCUACUUCCGGGUGAUGGUGGACAGUCUGGUAGAACAGGAGAUCCAGACAUCAGUAGCAACUCUGGAUGAAACUGAAGAACUCCCUAGAGAAUAUCUGGGAGCAAACUGGACGUUAGAAAAGGUUUUUGAGGAACUUCAAGCUACUGACAAAAAGAGAGUUCUGGAAGAGAAUCAAGAACAUUAUCAUAUAGUUCAAAAGUUUCUUAUCCUGGGAGACAUUGAUGGUUUGAUGGAUGAGUUUAGCAAAUGGCUUUCCAAAAGCAGAAACAAUCUACCUGGACACCUGCUUCGCUUUAUGACUCACCUUAUUUUGUUUUUCCGUACUCUGGGACUACAGACCAAGGAGGAAGUUUCUAUUGAAGUUUUAAAGACAUACAUACAGCUUUUAAUAAGAGAGAAACAUACAAAUCUUAUAGCAUUUUAUACCUGUCAUUUGCCUCAAGACCUAGCUGUUGCCCAGUAUGCAUUAUUUUUGGAAAGUGUUACAGAAUUUGAACAGCGCCACCAUUGCCUGGAGUUGGCUAAAGAAGCAGAUUUGGAUGUUGCAACAAUAACAAAAACUGUAGUUGAGAAUAUUCGAAAGAAAGAUAAUGGUGAAUUUAGUCAUCAUGACCUGGCCCCAGCCCUAGAUACUGGCACUACUGAGGAGGAUCGUUUAAAAAUUGAUGUAAUUGACUGGUUGGUAUUUGACCCAGCGCAGAGGGCAGAAGCACUGAAACAAGGCAAUGCAAUUAUGAGAAAAUUCUUGGCAUCAAAAAAGCACGAAGCUGCAAAAGAAGUAUUUGUGAAAAUUCCUCAGGAUUCUAUAGCAGAAAUCUAUAAUCAGUGCGAGGAACAAGGAAUGGAAAGUCCACUUCCUGCUGAAGAUGAUAAUGCUAUCCGAGAACAUUUGUGCAUCAGAGCUUAUUUGGAAGCCCAUGAAACCUUUAAUGAGUGGUUUAAGCAUAUGAAUUCAGUUCCACAAAAACCUGCUUUGAUACCUCAACCAACUUUUACUGAGAAAGUGGCUCAUGAACACAAAGAAAAGAAAUAUGAAAUGGAUUUUGGUAUUUGGAAAGGGCAUUUGGAUGCCCUAACUGCUGAUGUGAAGGAGAAAAUGUAUAACGUCUUGUUGUUUGUUGAUGGAGGGUGGAUGGUGGAUGUUAGAGAGGAUGCCAAAGAAGACCAUGAAAGAACACAUCAAAUGGUCUUACUGAGAAAGCUUUGUCUGCCAAUGUUGUGUUUUCUGCUUCAUACGAUAUUGCACAGUACUGGUCAGUAUCAGGAAUGCCUACAGUUAGCAGAUAUGGUAUCCUCUGAGCGCCACAAACUGUACCUGGUAUUUUCUAAGGAAGAGCUAAGGAAGUUGCUGCAGAAGCUCAGAGAGUCCUCUCUAAUGCUCCUAGACCAGGGACUUGACCCAUUAGGGUAUGAAAUUCAGUUAUAGUUUAAUCUUUGUAAUCUCACUAAUUUUCAUGAUAAAUGAAGUUUUUAAUAAAAUAUACUUGUUAUUAGUAAUUUUUUCUUUUGCAUUACCAUGUAAAAUUUAGACAUUUGAAUUUUGUACUUUUCAGAAUAUUAUCGUGACACUUUCAACAUGUAGGGAUAUCAGCGUUUCUCUGUGUGCUUGUUAAUAAAACUAUAUAAAAAUUAAAAUUUUCUGUUUUUACAAAUUCCAGGGUUGUCUCUUUUUCAUGUAAUAAGAAAAUUAAAUUUUCUGUUCUAGUUUUUUCUGUAAUCAUAAGCAUUCUGAUAUUUUAAAAUCAUAAAGAUGAUGGAAAGUAGAUUUAUUUUUAAGCCAGGUACGUAAUUUUUUAUUUAUCAUAAAAUUUAGUAUUUUUGAAUAUUAAAAUUAAGAAGAUGACUAUAACAAGAAUUUUUCUAACAUAACAUGCUAUUAUUAUUUUAGUUAUUUUGAAGACAUUUCUAGUUUAACUUUCAUUUAGCAAACUUCCUAUCAAAAUAAGAGCAUAUAAAGACUUAGCGUAGUACCUGGCACACAGUAAGCACUGAAUAUAUUGGAGAUUACAGAUCCCGCUCUUCUAAUAGGGGAAAUACCAUAAGUACAUUUAAAAGGUGUCAUUUAAAAAUACAAGUAGUGGCUGGGUGCAGUGGCUCACGUCUGUAACCCCAGCACUUCGGGAGGCCGAGGCAGGUGGAUCACCUGUCGUCAGGAGUUUGAGACCAGCCUGGCCAACAUGGUGAAACCCUGUCUCUACUAAAAAAAUACAAAAAUUAGCCGGGCAUGGUGGCAGGUGCCUGUAAUCCCAGCUACUCAGGGGAGGCUGAGGCAUGAGAAUCUCUUGAACCUGGAAGGCAGAGGUUGCAGUGAGCCGAGAUCACGCCACUGCACUCCAGCCUUGGGGACAGAGCGAGACACUGUCUCCAAAAAAAGAAAGAAUUACAAGUAGUCUGAGCAGGAAGAACCUCUCUCCAGCUGAAAAGACUCUCAGGAAGUAGUAUUGGUUUGGGGUUUGAGUAAUGCACUGAAUUUGCAAAGGCAAAGAGUGACACAAGAAGGAUGAGGCUCUAUAGAUUAAGAAAUCAGUAUGAGCAAGAAAUGAUAAAUGCUGGGCAUUAUUAUGAACCAACAAAUACACCAAAUAGGCUAGAGUGUAGGGCUUAUAAACAGGAGACAACUAAAAGAAUGUGAUUCUAAUAGAAAACAGUAAUUCCCCAAACUUGCUAAUCAUCUAAGGAAUUUCUUGAAUAUGUAUUUAUAGAUGCCACCCCUAGAGACAGCUGGCUUGGGAAGCCUGAGAUGGGAUCAUAGAAUUUGAUCAGUUCUAUAUUAUGUGCUUUUUUUGUUUUAUUUCUCUAAAGAAUUCAUCUUGUCUUCCUGUUUUCUUUAUUCUUACUAAUAUGCAAAUGAUUUUUACAGCUCAUGCAGUCCUGUAAUCAUGAUUAUUGCUAUGCUACUUUGCAAAAAAUAAAAACAAAAAAUUCAUACCAAAACAAAUACAGACUAGAUUUGGGGUGGGGAGGGGAAAUAAGUGAGUCUUAAAAGUAGUUUUGUUACUUGCAACAAACUGUAUAUAUAGAAACUUUGUACAACCCAGGGUGACUAUUUCCAAAGACUGUUACCUAUUUGUUGAACAACAGUGGGAAAACUACUUAGCCUAAAUGAGGAGGAGGAAUAUUGUAUGCUUCCAUCGUAACCGUAUGUGGGUAAAUGGACAAGGUCUGUCAUCUAUUUAGGAACUUGUUUUGCAUGUCCCCCACUCUGUAUUUGUCUUUUGUUGUGCCUUGUUUUUUGAAUGUCCUUUAAAAAACACAGCACAGAAACCCACUAAGGUUGUGGAAUUACAAAAUUCCUUCAACCUUAGACUCUUAAUUAGGAUGCCCUCAAAUGGACUUGUUUUUAAUUUUUAUUUAUUUAUUUAUUUUUGAGACAUGGUCUUGCUCUGUCUCCCAGGCCGGAGUGCAGUGGCAUGAUAUCUCACUGCAAACCUCCGCCUCCUGGGUUCAAGCGAUUCUCCUGCCUCAGCCUCCCUAGUAGCUGGGAUUACAGGCGCCUGCCACCACGCCUGGCUAAUUUUUGUAUUUUUAGUAGAGACGGGGUUUUGCCAUGUUGGCCAGGCUGGUCUCAAACUCUUGACCUCAAGUGAUCCACUCGCCUCGAUCUCUCAAAGUGCUGGGAUUACAGGCAUAAGCCACUGCACCCAGCCAAUUGGACUCCUUUGAGUCCUUAGGGAGUCAAUGUGUGUGUUGCUGCUUAUUUAAAUACAGUUCAGUUGGAGCCCCAAGAGUGCCAAUGUGCUCCUCACAAUUCCCAAAUGCCUCUCUUCCUGAACACCAGAAGUGGUGGGCACCUGAGUGGGAAAUUUCAGGCAACUUAAUUUAGUUCCUCAGUGCCUACUCUUGAAGAACUGGGUUUUCAUUCUAGAGAGGAAACUCAGGGAAGGGCGUGUUGCCUAUCACAGGUUCGCAUACUAAGUUUUAAAAACUUUUCUUGGUGUGACUUAUGCCAAGGAAUUAUGAAGACUUUUUCCUUGAGCAUUGCAUGAAGGCUACAAAGUUGGAACAGGCAUGUCCUGGGUGUGAAAGUUUUAAUUUCCCUACCUCAUUUAUUUAUUUAAUUUAGAGAUGGGGGUCUCACUAUGUUGCCCAUCCCGGCUUCCAACUCCUGGGCUCAAGCAAUCCUCCCACGUCAGUCUCUCAAAUAGCUGGGACUACAGGCCCACGCCACCAUGCCCUACUUCCUCAUUUAUUUUAAAUUUUUUGUACCACAGUCUCUCUUUUUAAUUUUAUGACUGCUGAAUUAAUCCUAGACUCUGUCUUAAAACUAAGAAUUGAUGUAUUGGCAGGAACAGCUGGACAUUCAAGAUGUUUUUGUGAUUCCUUUUUUAAAAAUCUCCUUUUGUACCUGUAAUAUCUACAAUAUAUAAUCUUUCUUUAUCGACUUAAGGAGGAAGGAGAAAGGAAGAACCUGACUUCUGUGUGAAGGACCUUACUGUCGAUCAAGACUGUUACUCAAAGUUCUAUCUCUUAGUCAUUGCACCUGACCUGAUCCAAAACAUAUAUAUAUAUUUGUAUGCACCCCUAGAGACAGCUGUAUAUAUAUACGGUUUUGCCAGGUUGUACGUUUUUUUCUCGAGUUGUAAGUGAACACAGUAGCACUCGUUUACAUUGUCAAGGGGACAUCUUUAGAGAACACAUUUUCUCACUGUUGAGCUAAUAAUGCUUUGUGAAUGUAUGAUCUAAGGAGAAACCCUUGUAGUUAUACCCGAUGAUGCUGUCUGUUGGAAAGUAAAUUUUGAAUGUCUUUUUCCAAAAAUAAAAAAUAAAAACAUG